GGAGAGCCUGCCGGUGGGAGCUGGAAGCAGGCUCCCGGCUGAGCGCCCCAGCCCGAAAGGCAGGGUCUGGGUGCGGGAAGAGGGCUCGGAGCUGCCUUCCUGCUGCCUUGGGGCCGCCCAGAUGAGGGAACAGCCCGAUUUGCCUGGUUCUGAUUCUCCAGGCUGUCGUGGUUGUGGAAUGCAAACGCCAGCACAUAAUGGAAACAGGACCUGAAGACCCUUCCAGCAUGCCAGAGGAAAGUUCCCCCAGGCGGACCCCGCAGAGCAUUCCCUACCAGGACCUCCCUCACCUGGUCAAUGCAGACGGACAGUACCUCUUCUGCAGGUACUGGAAACCCACAGGCACACCCAAGGCCCUCAUCUUUGUGUCCCAUGGAGCCGGAGAGCACAGUGGCCGCUAUGAAGAGCUGGCUCGGAUGCUGAUGGGGCUGGACCUGCUGGUGUUCGCCCACGACCAUGAGCUGAACAGGAGAAAAUCCUUGUAAGUGGGAGAGAUGCAGACUAGAUUCAGAAGGAUCUUCCCCUGGAAGGAUGCGAGCACCAAGAGAAUGCCAGAAUUUAUACAUUUUUCUCCUCUGAAACCAUACAAAGGGAGGGAAUGGGAGAAGGCGGGGAGCGAGCACGUGCUGGAAACCCACCUUUUGCCAGUUGGCCACGGACAGAGCGAAGGGGAGAGGAUGGUAGUGUCUGACUUCCACGUUUUCGUCAGGGAUGUGUUGCAGCAUGUGGAUUCCAUGCAGAAAGACUACCCUGGGCUUCCUGUCUUCCUUCUGGGCCACUCCAUGGGAGGCGCCAUCGCCAUCCUCACGGCCGCAGAGAGGCCGGGCCACUUCGCCGGCAUGGUACUCAUUUCGCCUCUGGUUCUUGCCAAUCCUGAAUCUGCAACAACUUUCAAGGUCCUUGCUGCGAAAGUGCUCAACCUUGUGCUGCCAAACUUGUCCCUCGGGCCCAUCGACUCCAGCGUGCUCUCUCGGAAUAAGACAGAGGUCGACAUUUAUAACUCAGACCCCCUGAUCUGCCGGGCAGGGCUGAAGGUGUGCUUCGGCAUCCAACUGCUGAAUGCCGUCUCACGGGUGGAGCGCGCCCUCCCCAAGCUGACUGUGCCCUUCCUGCUGCUCCAGGGCUCUGCCGAUCGCCUAUGUGACAGCAAAGGGGCCUACCUGCUCAUGGAGUUAGCCAAGAGCCAGGACAAGACUCUCAAGAUUUAUGAAGGUGCCUACCAUGUUCUCCACAAGGAGCUUCCUGAAGUCACCAACUCCGUCUUCCAUGAAAUAAACAUGUGGGUCUCUCAAAGGACAGCCACGGCAGGAACUGCGUCCCCACCCUGAAUGCAUUGGCCGGUGCCCGGCUCAUGGUCUGGGGGAUGCAGGCAGGGGAAGGGCAGAGAUGGCUUCUCAGAUAUGGCUUGCCAAAAAAAAAAAAAAAAAAAAAUCAGAAAUUGGAGAAAUCCUUAGCACAAUUUUCUAAAAAAUAACAGACAUUUUUGUUAUACAUUAGACUAUCAGACACUGGACCUACCUUAAUGGUUAGACACUUUAUGCAAAAAAAGAGAAAGGUCCCAGGUGAUUUUCCACAAAGAAUGUGCUAAAAUGUCCACUGAAAACAAAGCCAAGCCUCUGCCCUGCCUCUCCCAGCUCCCACAAGGGUUCCAGGAAUUCCUGGUGUUCCCAGGACACCAGACUGCAAUAACUGGAGGCGCCUCCUUCCUGCCCACCCUUCGCUCACGCCCCAGCGCCCUCUCUGACCAGCCUCCGCUUGGUGGCCUUCCUCUGGCCGUGUGAUGAGGUGGUUGCUGUCUCCAUAGGGGCCAGCUCCCCAGGGCAGACUCACGUGCCCCUCUGAGGCUCAGAAAAUGCCCAGCCCUUCCUCAAAAUGAGCAGCCACCCAUGACUUUGUGGGCUCCUUGUUAGCCUGAGACCAGGCUUUGCAGAGGGGCGGGGGGUGAGGCUUAGCCCAGAAGGAGAACUGAGCAGGAAACCAAGGCUCUUCUCUGUCCCCUGCCCUUCCCCUCCUGCCAGGGGGAGGCUCAGGUUGGUCCCCGAGUGCCGCCUGUACUCACAAAGGCUGCCUUUCCUCUAGAGUCACUAAUUUUACCUGAUGCUAUGAGAGAAUCAUAUUGAAGAUGAAAUGUCUAAUAUAUAAUGUAUAUUUUAAAGCAGAGACUAUUUUGGUGGAUAGGUGGGAGGGAGCAAGGGGAGUUUGAGGGAAUCAGAGCUUGAUGCUACUGUACAGAACUGGACAGGUUGGGCCGGCAGUGGUGGGGCCAGAGGGCUCUGUGCUCUAGGAGCUAAGCCAGCAGCCCCCGAGAGGGGACUUGGCUGGGCCUUUCCUAUGGGCAAGGCCCAGUGCUCUUCCUGCCCACCAGGGACCAUGGAGCAGUGGCACCCUAUGGGGCUAUGAUCCCUAGGCCUGGGCCUGGGCCUGCCUAUGGCCCAGAGCUACCCUGGGAGUGUCAGUGCUAGCAGCACAGCUACCUCUGGUGGCAGGAGAAGAGAGGCCCAGCACAGCAGCAGGCCAGGCCUUCCUGUCCAGGUCUGCAUGGAGCACUCGGUGACCCAGAGCAGGGACUGGAGGCACCCCCAGCCCUGCCCCAGGCCACAGCAGGACAGGCCGGGACAGGCCUCACCCAAGGCCAAGGCUGGCAUCAGCCAAUCAUUCAGAGCUGAGGCCCUGGGCCUAGCCUGCCCUUCUCAGGUGCCAAUACCACCCCAGCCCUGCCCUUGGCCUCACUUUUUCCCAGCAAUAAGUGGGGUUCACCACCCGCCUCGGGAAUACUUUCCCCUUCUAAAUGGGACUUGCUGUUACCUCAGGAGGCUCCUUAGUGCAAAUAUGACCCUGGUCAGGGCUUUGCCACCGUUGAAGCCCUGCAGAAGGUGCAAUGUAGGGGUUCUGGGGCCACAGAGGAGAGGCCACUUCCCACCAGGACCCCCAACAUGAAGUCUAGGCCUCAGGGGCUCCCGCCCUUCUUCCUCCAGCAGCGGGAACUGCCACUGCUCUCCCAGGCCCUGUUCUGGAGGCUAACCUUGGUUCCUGGAGAGUGUGCCCCUCCACCCUCCCUCCAGCAGCCCUGAUCACACCAUGAGAGCCAGGAACGGGUCACCCUGCUGAAGAUCACUCUGUGCCCUGGGGGAGGAGCCAAGCCCUCACCCCACAAGGGGCAGGUGGGGGCUUGGUUGCUGACCCGGCCCAAGUCCCCACAGAGCACCUUCUGUAGCUCCAGCUUGUCUCCCUGGCUUCUCUUUGAAGGAGAAAAAUGUAAAAUAUGCACUGAGAAAGCCAGCCCCGCCUGCUUAGUCAGCCCCGGCAGCAGGGCAGCCAUGGGAACUCAGGAAAAGCAGGAACCCUUUCCAAAAGCCCAGAGAUGCCCUGGGCUCAGAUCUGUAAUUCUCCCAGGAGCUGUGAUAGAGCAGGCCACACAAAGUCCCUACGCCUCCCUGCUGCCUCCCCCAGAUGCAUGUGGUGGCAUCACCAUUCCCCAAAUUGAAUAUCAGCAUGCGGCCUGACCAGGGACUCUUUAGAUGCAUGAAUUUAUUUAUAUGAAGGCUCUCACAGAGACACACACAGCACUUCAGUAGCAUUUGCAUUCCUGGUUAAAGAAUCACCAAUAUUUAAAAUAAAAACUUUCCUGAAAUUGGGACUGUCAUGUUAUCCAGAAGGGCUGGUACAUCCGCCCACCAUGUCCCCCUGCUGGGUCAGGAGCCAACACAGGACCCUGCGUGUGAGCGUGCCUGACAUCUCACGCACGGCCACUCCAGAGCCGGUCCCUGUCCUUGGAAAGCUGUGAAGCCUUGCGUUGAGUUCCUUCUCGAUACUGACGGCUCCGUGCUGACAUUCUGAGCUCUGGAGUCACACCAGCGCAGGGGCGUGGAGGAACUGAGGUUUGGAAGGAAUGCCAGGUCUCGCACAGCUUGGCCUCGAGAAGGUGAGAGGAAGGCAAAGGCCAGGGAGGGGACCCAGAGAGGCCUGGCACACAAGGCCCAAGCACCACCGUCAACACAGCCCAGUCCAUACAGAAAUGGGUUUCAUGCCUGAAAAGCUUUUUACAGAAAGAUGCCGCCUGUAGCCAGUGACAGCCGCAACCCUACAGGCCUCAGUUCCUUGCAGAGGUGAGGGGUAGAGAGUCAGCCUCCCUCCCUUCCAGCAGCGACCCAGCUUCCCUCCACUUCCAGGUGGUGCUGGGCUCACCGAGGGAGCACUGGUGGGUGCUCUGAAAACCCACAGGAUCCCACCUCCAGGCCCACCUGGGUCCCAUCUCACUCUCUUCUUCUUUCACCAAUUGCUAACAUAGACCUUGUUGGGAUCACGAUGGCUUCACAAGCCAGCUGUUGGGUUUGCUAUGUCACUGUGGCUCAGUCACAUCCCUGCGUGUAUACUGUCUGCGGGGCACAUAUGUAUCCAUUUAGAGCUAAAGGAAUCAGUGUACACUACAGCUAAUCCUAAUAAAUCCGAUGUUUUCGGAA